UCGGAAAAGCGCAGUAUUCGGGUGGGAGUGACCCGAUUCUCCAGGUGCGUCCUUCACCCCUUUCUUUGACUAGGAAAGGGAACUCCCUGACCCCUUGUGCUUCCCAAGUGAGGCAAUGCCUCGCCCUGCUUUGGCUCGUGCACGGUGCGUGCACCCGCUGACCUGGGCCCACUCUCUGGCACUUCCUAGUGAGAUGAACCCGGUACCUCAGAUGGAAAUGCAGAAAUCACCCGUCUUCUGCGUCGCUCACGCUGGGAGCUGUAGACUGGAGCUGUUCCUAUUCGGCCAUCUUGGCUCCUCCCUCAGUUCCAUUAACAAAUGAUGUGAUGCAGUCUAUGUUGCAAGUUGGACUACCAUUUAUCCAAGACGACGAAUUGUGCUCUGGAAUGCAGAAUACAGCACUGGGAGUUGGCCUCAGGACUUCAAGAUUUGCUGCAGGCAUUCAGAAGAGUUAUUUAAAUUCUCUGGACUUCAGUUUUCUCACCUACAAAUACAAACAAAGGGAUACUGAUUUCACUGUGGCUAAGCAGCUGCUUAUGACCUUGAACAAAGCAGAAGUGUUGGAAUGCCUUCCUGCUGUCUGUAUGGACCUGCUCUUGCCAGUUACUGCACAAAGAAAUAGUUUAAUUCCACUUGGAAUACAGGUCUUUACACUUGGACUAGAACUGUAACAUCUGCUGUCCUGGUUGCCAGGCUUUUGAACAUACACUGUUGGUUCUCCUGGAUCUUCACCUUACCAACUGCAGAUCUUGGGACUCAUCAGCCUCAAUAAUUAUAUUAAAUUAACACCAUUUGAAAGAGAACAUUGUUUUCAUCAUGAAUGCUAAUAAAGAUGAAAGACUUAAAGCCAGAAGCCAAGAUUUUCACCUUUUUCCUGCUUUGAUGAUGCUAAGCAUGACCAUGUUGUUUCUUCCAGUCACUGGCACUUUGAAGCAAAAUAUUCCAAGACUCAAGCUAACCUACAAAGACUUGCUGCUUUCAAAUAGCUGUAUUCCCUUUUUGGGUUCAUCAGAAGGACUGGAUUUUCAAACUCUUCUCUUAGAUGAGGAAAGAGGCAGGCUGCUCUUGGGAGCCAAAGACCACAUCUUUCUACUCAGUCUGGUUGACUUAAACAAAAAUUUUAAGAAGAUUUAUUGGCCUGCUGCAAAGGAACGGGUGGAAUUAUGUAAAUUAGCUGGGAAAGAUGCCAAUACAGAAUGUGCAAAUUUCAUCAGAGUACUUCAGCCCUAUAACAAAACUCACAUAUAUGUGUGUGGAACUGGAGCAUUUCAUCCAAUAUGUGGGUAUAUUGAUCUUGGAGUCUACAAGGAGGAUAUUAUAUUCAAACUAGACACACAUAAUUUGGAGUCUGGCAGACUGAAAUGUCCUUUCGAUCCUCAGCAGCCUUUUGCUUCAGUAAUGACAGAUGAGUACCUCUACUCUGGAACAGCUUCUGAUUUCCUUGGCAAAGAUACUGCAUUCACUCGAUCCCUUGGGCCUACUCAUGACCACCACUACAUCAGAACUGACAUUUCAGAGCACUACUGGCUCAAUGGAGCAAAAUUUAUUGGAACUUUCUUCAUACCAGACACCUACAAUCCAGAUGAUGAUAAAAUAUAUUUCUUCUUUCGUGAAUCAUCUCAAGAAGGCAGUACCUCCGAUAAAACCAUCCUUUCUCGAGUUGGAAGAGUUUGUAAGAAUGAUGUAGGAGGACAACGCAGCCUGAUAAACAAGUGGACGACUUUUCUUAAGGCCAGACUGAUUUGCUCAAUUCCUGGAAGUGAUGGGGCAGAUACUUACUUUGAUGAGCUUCAAGAUAUUUAUUUACUCCCCACAAGAGAUGAAAGAAAUCCUGUAGUAUAUGGAGUCUUUACUACAACCAGCUCCAUCUUCAAAGGCUCUGCUGUUUGUGUGUAUAGCAUGGCUGACAUCAGAGCAGUUUUUAAUGGUCCAUAUGCUCAUAAGGAAAGUGCAGACCAUCGUUGGGUGCAGUAUGAUGGGAGAAUUCCUUAUCCACGGCCUGGUACAUGUCCAAGCAAAACCUAUGACCCACUGAUUAAGUCCACCCGAGAUUUUCCAGAUGAUGUCAUCAGUUUCAUAAAGCGGCACUCUGUGAUGUAUAAGUCCGUAUACCCAGUUGCAGGAGGACCAACGUUCAAGAGAAUCAAUGUGGAUUACAGACUGACACAGAUAGUGGUGGAUCAUGUCAUUGCAGAAGAUGGCCAGUACGAUGUAAUGUUUCUUGGAACAGACAUUGGAACUGUCCUCAAAGUUGUCAGCAUUUCAAAGGAAAAGUGGAAUAUGGAAGAGGUAGUGCUGGAGGAGUUGCAGAUAUUCAAGCACUCAUCAAUCAUCUUGAACAUGGAAUUGUCUCUGAAGCAGCAACAAUUGUACAUUGGUUCCCGAGAUGGAUUGGUUCAGCUCUCCUUGCACAGAUGCGACACUUAUGGGAAAGCUUGCGCAGACUGUUGUCUUGCCAGAGACCCCUACUGUGCCUGGGAUGGAAAUGCAUGCUCUCGAUAUGCUCCUACUUCUAAAAGGAGAGCUAGACGCCAAGAUGUAAAAUAUGGCGACCCAAUCACCCAGUGCUGGGACAUCGAAGACAGCAUUAGUCAUGAAACUGCUGAUGAAAAGGUGAUUUUUGGCAUUGAAUUUAACUCAACCUUUCUGGAAUGUAUACCUAAAUCCCAACAAGCAACUAUUAAAUGGUAUAUCCAGAGGUCAGGGGAUGAGCAUCGAGAGGAGUUGAAGCCCGAUGAAAGAAUCAUCAAAACGGAAUAUGGGCUACUGAUUCGAAGUUUGCAGAAGAAGGAUUCUGGGAUGUAUUACUGCAAAGCCCAGGAGCACACUUUCAUCCACACCAUAGUGAAGCUGACUUUGAAUGUCAUUGAGAAUGAACAGAUGGAAAAUACCCAGAGGGCAGAGCAUGAGGAGGGGAAGGUCAAGGAUCUAUUGGCUGAGUCACGGUUGAGAUACAAAGACUACAUCCAAAUCCUUAGCAGCCCAAACUUCAGCCUCGACCAGUACUGCGAACAGAUGUGGCACAGGGAGAAGCGGAGACAGAGAAACAAGGGGGGCCCAAAGUGGAAGCACAUGCAGGAAAUGAAGAAGAAACGAAAUCGAAGACAUCACAGAGACCUGGAUGAGCUCCCUAGAGCUGUAGCCACGUAGUUUUCUACUUAAUUUAAAGAAAAGAAUUCCUUACCUAUAAAAACAUUGCCUUCUGUUUUGUAUAUCCCUUAUAGUAAUUCAUAAAUGCUUCCCAUGGAGUUUUGCUAAGGCACAAGACAAUAAUCUGAAUAAGACAAUAUGUGAUGAAUAUAAGAAAGGGCAAAAAAUUCAUUUGAACCAGUUUUCCAAGAACAAAUCUUGCACAAGCAAAGUAUAAGAAUUAUCCUAAAAAUAGGGGGUUUACAGUUGUAAAUGUUUUAUGUUUUGAGUUUUGGAAUUUAUUGUCAUGUAAAUAGUUGAGCUAAGCAAGCCCCGAAUUUGAUAGUGUAUAAGGUGCUUUAUUCCCUCGAAUGUCCAUUAAGCAUGGAAUUUACCAUGCAGUUGUGCUAUGUUCUUAUGAACAGAUAUAUCAUUCCUAUUGAGAACCAGCUACCUUGUGGUAGGGAAUAAGAGGUCAGACACAAAUUAAGACAACUCCCAUUAUCAACAGGAACUUUCUCAGUGAGCCAUUCACUCCUGGAGAAUGGUAUAGGAAUUUGGAGAGGUGCAUUAUUUCUUUCUGGCCACUGGGGUUAAAUUUAGUGUACUACAACAUUGAUUUACUGAAGGGCACUAAUGUUUCCCCCAGGAUUUCUAUUGACUAGUCAGGAGUAACAGGUUCACAGAGAGAAGUUGGUGCUUAGUUAUGUGUUUUUUAGAGUAUAUACUAAGCUCUACAGGGACAGAAUGCUUAAUAAAUACUUUAAUAAGAUAUGGGAAAAUAUUUUAAUAAAACAAGGAAAACAUAAUGAUGUAUAAUGCAUCCUGAUGGGAAGGCAUGCAGAUGGGAUUUGUUAGAAGACAGAAGGAAAGACAGCCAUAAAUUCUGGCUUUGGGGAAAACUCAUAUCCCCAUGAAAAGGAAGAACAAUCACAAAUAAAGUGAGAGUAAUGUAAUGGAGCUCUUUUCACUAGGGUAUAAGUAGCUGCCAAUUUGUAAUUCAUCUGUUAAAAAAAAUCUAGAUUAUAACAAACUGCUAGCAAAAUCUGAGGAAACAUAAAUUCUUCUGAAGAAUCAUAGGAAGAGUAGACAUUUUAUUUAUAACCAAUGAUAUUUCAGUAUAUAUUUUCUCUCUUUUAAAAAAUAUUUAUCAUACUCUGUAUAUUAUUUCUUUUUACUGCCUUUAUUCUCUCCUGUAUAUUGGAUUUUGUGAUUAUAUUUGAGUGAAUAGGAGAAAACAAUAUAUAACACACAGAGAAUUAAGAAAAUGACAUUUCUGGGGAGUGGGGAUAUAUAUUUGUUGAAUAACAGAACGAGUGUAAAAUUUUAACAACGGAAAGGGUUAAAUUAACUCUUUGACAUCUUCACUCAACCUUUUCUCAUUGCUGAGUUAAUCUGUUGUAAUUGUAGUAUUGUUUUUGUAAUUUAACAAUAAAUAAGCCUGCUACAUGUAAAAAGAACCAAACUCACAAUAUUAACAUAAACAUCUUUCAUAUUUUGUUAGUACUUUCAAAUGUUUUCAAUUUGACUUUCCCUCUGAAUAUGCAUGGUGUGUUUCCUGUCUGUUUAAGCAGAACUCACCUUUCCUUCUUGUAACACAGAACCCUUAGCCUUCUUCUGUUUUGCCUUUUCACGCCCUUUAUAGUGUGAAAUGAAAAAUUAGUCACUUCCUCACAUGGAAGGCAGCUUUUCAGAAAAUAACAGACAUUGCUCGUUUCUCAUGCAUUCUACAUAUCUUGAAAGAAAAGUCUGUGAGAAAACCCUGUGAUUAGAGGGCAACUUAAUGCAAGAUCUGUGGCUCUAUGUUGAGAGCAUUCUCUCUCUGUUAUUUUUAUUUUAUUUGCAUUGCUUACCUAUCUCAAAGUAGUCAAACUGAUAUAUGAGAUUGAGUACUCCCUUUUGAUAUUAUACUGAUGAAUAUUUGUAGGUGUUUCACUAUAAGGAACAGCUAAGGAAUAAUUUUAAUAAAAGUGAACCAGAACAAAUCACUCAUUUAAAAAGUAAUUCAGAAGAACAGUGUGGCAUGAUCAGACUUCUAAUUGAAUAGCGUAACAACAGUGUUUGUAAUUAUAGAUUUGCUUGGACAAAAUAUUCCAGGAACUCAUAGCGAGCUCAAAGCAAUUAAGUGGGAACAUUUUUAAUUUAAAAAAAAUUUCCAAAUAUUUGUGGGUCCGACAGUAAUGAUCAAAAUAUGAAUGACUUUGGAAAAUUUACAUGAAGCUCAAGUGUUAGGAUUGACUUAUGAAAAUAAAUUUUAUUUCUAUCCAAAUUUGAAUGUCCAAACCAUUUUUUAGUUACUUCUUUCUAAUCCUAGUUAUUCAGACAAAAUUUGGAAACUUAUUUUAUGACCACAUCUAAUAUUCUGGCUGCUUUGGAUACAAUACUCUUGAUUUAUGAUAAUUAGUUAAAAUAUAUUAAAAAUAUUAUUAGUAAAAUAAAAUUUCACACAAUAAAAAACAACAUAGAGUACACAUAUUUAUAUGUAUUUUUAAAGAUAAAGAAUAUCUAAAAUGUGUUUUUUUCUUAGCUUUUUAGUUGUCUAGAACAUUUAGAGAAAGAGUAUGAAUAUAUUAAAUCCACAAACACACUAUAUACUUCCUCACCACUGACUAUUUUAUCAAAUUUGCCUUAAAAUAAUGAAAAAGAAAAGUAUAGUUAAUGGUUUCAAAUAUGCUAAGAAAUUGACUCUGCGGAGGGGAUCUUAAAAUGCCUGUUUACUCAUGUUUUCGUAUUUUUCUUGUCUCUAAUACUUUUGUCUUUGUCUGCCUUGUGUGUUCUUUUCUGAAUUUCAUUUCAGCAAUUUAUGCUGCUAAAUAGAAUCCCGCAUGUCUGCAUUCAUUUACAUUCAACUUAUUGUAAAUUUUGAGAUUUUAUUUAGAAAUGAAUUGUCUAAUUAAUUUAUGUAGAGUCCUUUUUUCCAAAGAGCUCAAAACACUACAUCCACAUUAUUGACUUUUGGAAACCAACCAAAUUACUUAAGAAAUGGAAAAGUAGUCACAGAGAAAUUUAGUAAUUUGCAAAAGCCACAACAGUAGUGGAAGAAUUAAAAUUCAUAAAGUCUCAUCAUUCUGUUGGCUAAAAUAAUGCUCUUUACAAUAUGCUGGCUACAAAAUGGUCUUACUCUUGAAUUUUGCUUUUGGUUCAUAUUUUGGUUCUUCAUAUUCUAGUAUGUUUUGUUCCUGCUGAAUUUUACAGACUCAGCUAAACAAUAAGUUAUUAGUAGUCACUUGUUUUCAUUAUCAUAAUUGAAUUUCCAAGAACAACUUGAUAUCAUUCAGCUGUCCAAAAAAUAAUAAGAGCAUUCAUUAAAUACUGAUUUUCUUAAACUUAAAUGUUGUAUUUCAUAUUUAUUUAUAUAAUACAAAUGGAAAUCAAAACUGAAAUAGCCUCCCUUUAGAAUGUCACAUUUUUCUUAGAAAACAUUUUGGAAUUGGUUAACCUUAUUGGGAAUGGAUAAUUUAGAAACAAACCAAAAAAAAAAAAAGAUAUUUGAAGUGUUUUUAUAGGAGAUGUAUUUUUAUCAUAGUAAAUGAUCACAAUUUUAAAUAAUUCAUCUUACAAGUCAGGUAAAAUAAAAUCGAUUCCCAGAUUCCAUACAUUAGGAGUGCAAAGACAGGAUCAUACACAUGACUUAUACCUCUCAUUUAAAUAUUUUAUAGUAUAAAGUAUUUAUGGAAAGGGUUUGAGAUAGAUGAUUUUUGGGAAAGGGCAAAAUGUGUCAGAUGCCCUAGUUAAUCAUGUAAUUUAAUUCUGGUAUUGUGAGUGGUUAGCAAUCAAUUUUGAAUUUAUAAUUCUGCUAUUUUAAAAGAAAUGUAGUCUUGUAGUAUGAAAUAAUUAAAAAUUGUUAAAUGUAUAUUUUGGUUGUAUUAUAAUAAAAUGCAAACAUGACUGUUCUAUGAUUAUAAAAA